AGGAGACGAACCCGGAAGUGAGAUGCAAGGCGGCGAUUUUCCCUUCUGUCAGGUGGGUUGUUAUUCCCUGUCCCGGACCUCGCUUUUUGAUGGACCGGCGCCAUCUAAGAACUCCUGAGCCCGUGGGGGUGGGUAGCCUGUGGACACAGGCCGAGCCCUGCAGGUCAGGCCGCUUCGUGGUCCCCAGAUCUUGAUGAACAAAGCAGUCAUAAUUCAUCUCUAGAAAGAUUUAUAUCCUGGCAUUUGAAAUGCUUUUUAUUUAGAAUAGUAGUAAAAAAUGGAAAAAGAAAAAGGAAAUGAUGAUGGAAUACCAGACCAAGAGAAUUCCUUGGAUUUUUCUGAACACUUUAACCAACUUGAAUUGUUGGAAACACAUGGACACCUUAUUCCUACUGGUACUCAAAGUCUUUGGGUAGGCAAUUCUGAUGAAGAUGAGGAGCAAGAUGACAAAAAUGAAGAGUGGUAUCGAUUGCAAGAAAAAAAAAUGGAAAAAGACCCAAGCAGAUUGCUUCUUUGGGCUGCUGAAAAAAAUCGGCUUACCACAGUGCGGAGACUCCUUUCUGAAAAGGCCACUCACGUGAACACUAGGGAUGAAGAUGAGUAUACCCCUCUUCAUCGAGCAGCCUACAGUGGACACUUAGAUAUUGUUCAGGAGCUCAUUGCACAGGGGGCCGAUGUUCAUGCAGUGACUGUGGAUGGCUGGACGCCCCUGCACAGUGCUUGUAAGUGGAAUAAUACCAGAGUGGCUUCUUUCUUACUGCAGCAUGAUGCAGAUAUCAAUGCCCAAACAAAAGGCCUCUUGACCCCCUUGCAUCUUGCUGCUGGGAACAGAGACAGCAAGGAUACCCUAGAACUCCUCCUGAUGAACCGUUACGUCAAACCAGGGCUGAAAAACAACUUGGAAGAAACUGCAUUUGAUAUUGCCAGGAGGACAAGUAUCUAUCACUACCUCUUUGAAAUUGUGGAAGGCUGUACAAAUUCUUCACCUCAGUCUUAACAAUUCUAGUAAUUUUCCUAAGUUUCUAAAUACCAGUGCCUCCUGUGUGUGAGAUGUAUUCCCAUAAUCAAAGUUGACGUCAAACAUCUUACUACAAAAAUUCAGUGACAUUCAUUAUAACAUUCUUCCAAGUGAAUUGCCUGACUUUGAUGUCAAAAUGUAUUUGAAAGUAAUUUGCAUAUAUCUUUAAUUAUUUCUGUGGAGUUUGUGAUUUUUUUAUCAGAAAUAAUUUUAAUGUGUGUAUACUUAAAAACUUGACACGGGUUGUACAGAAACUGGUAUUUUUGGUGCUGAUACAAGAGAAAUGUAUUUUUAAAUAUCCCACAUCCUGGAUCUUUGUUGGGUAUUUAGUAUAUUGACAUAUAUUUUUAUAAGGUGAGGUAACUCAGAACUUAAUUUAAAAGUCUUAAAUAUUCUGAUACAAUUCAGCUGUCUUCUCUACCUUACCAUAGCCAGUUGCUUUCAUUUUAAACCAGAGCAAGUAACAUAUUAGUGACUUGAAUCUUCAUAAGUUAAAGUAAAAAACAGCAAAAAACCUAGAUCUUUGUCUUUUAGAACACAGACCAUUUUCAGGAAAGCAGUUAGCUAAGUGUUUAAUUCAUGAAUAUUGUAUACUGCAUCCCCUACCACAAUUUACACAAUCCUGUGGAUAGUCCUACCUCACCCUGGUCAACCUACAUGAUCCUUAAGCUAAUGGCGAAUCACGAUGACCUUGUAGACAUGCACACAACUAUACCUUUGUCCAACAGAUCAUAAUAUAUCUGCUAUCCAACUGGUUUUACCUGCCUAAUCCUACUGAUUUGGGCACUGCUUGUAUAGUCUCUCAAGUUCACAGGAAAUGUUGAUUUUCUAAGGUCCUCAUUUUUACAGAGUAUACAGGCAAAGUGACAGGGGAAAAGGAAUUAGUCUAAGAGUAAGGGGAUGAUUAUUAUAUUGAGGCUAAAACCACAAAGUGGCUCAGGCUUUAAAAAAAAAACACUGUGGAUAAUGACAAAAAGCAUAAGUAAAAAUAUUUGAGAAAAAUAAAGUACAAGUUUUGAACAACA